GCGAACGUCUGUGUAACUUGGAGGAGGGCAGCCCGGGCAGCGGCACCUACACCCGCCACGGCUACAUCUUUUCGUCGCUUGCCGGCUGUCUGAUGAAGAGCAGCGAGAAUGGCGCGGUAAAGGAAGCGGCAUGCCAUCUCCCCUCUGUUUUUCCCUUAGGCUGCCCUUGAGUUCCAGUCCUUAGGCAUGGGCACUGCGGACGCGUCUUUAGUGCCUCAGUGGUACAAUGUUGGUCUCUUAGUUUCUUCUAGCCGUAUCGCCGCUGUGGUGCACUUAGCCACCACACACUAGUUGUGUUGAUCUCGCUUGGUUGUGCUGCUGACCCUCGGGGAGGGAAGUUGGGACAAAAGCAGAUGCGAACUCAGUAUCCCAUCCCAGCCCAGCUCAGCCCAGCACUUCCAGUGGUGUCUGUAGUGAGAGAAACAGAGUCCCAGUUACUGCCAGAUGUGGGAGCUAUUGUAACCUGUAAGGUCUCUAGCAUCAAUUCACGCUUUGCCAAAGUACACAUCCUGUAUGUGGGGUCCAUGCCUCUUAAGAACUCUUUUCGAGGAACUAUCCGCAAGGAAGAUGUCCGAGCAACUGAAAAAGACAAGGUUGAAAUUUAUAAGAGUUUCCGCCCAGGUGACAUUGUCUUGGCCAAAGUGAUCUCCUUAGGUGAUGCACAGUCCAACUACCUGCUAACCACCGCCGAGAACGAGCUGGGAGUGGUGGUAGCCCACAGUGAGUCAGGUAUCCAGAUGGUUCCCAUCAGCUGGUGUGAGAUGCAGUGCCCUAAGACCCACACUAAAGAAUUCCGGAAAGUAGCCCGAGUACAACCCGAAUUCUUGCAGACCUAAGAAGCCACUUUUUACCCUAUGGAAGGGGGUAAGCUGUUCCUGAGUAUAACACCAAGAUGCUGCUGUCUUUAUUCAAACACCUGGCGUCGGCCAACAGCCACUUCCAGAAAAAUCUUCCAGUUUACGCUGUAGAUGGAACAUGUUUCUGUGAACCUAUCAGUGGAUUUCAUUCUCUUGAGUAAUAAAUCUUAUCUUUUCAAGGCACCAACAAACAAAACUGUGAUAUUGGAAAUAGCCUAUCCCUCCUGACAGUCCUUAUAAAUACAUAUUUUUUGCUAUGAUAAAACUUUUUUACUAAAAGGAUGUUAUAGAGUCUGUUGUCUUAAGCAGAGAAAGACAUCUAAAUGGUGUCAGGACAUUUCAGUACUUCUGCUUAUUGAGUACUUACUGUGCUAGGCACUGAGUCAGGUGCUUUACAUACGUCCCCUUCAUUUAGGUACAUUGUGAUUUAAUGAAAAUUUGAGGACACGUGGUGAUACAGAUAGCAUGUGAGGCAGGCAUGGUGGCUCAUGUUUGUAAAUCCCAGCACUUUGGGA